AGUGCCCUGCCGUCCAGCCCAGCCCCUUUCCAGCAGGAAGCCCAGCCCUCGAACUUGAGAGGGGGACUGCACCCGGCUUUACUCACCUGAGCCCUGGCCGCGGCUGGGGCCUCUGAAGAGCUGACAGCCCAGCUUCUUGUGGUCCAUGAAGGCAGUGAUGGCCUCCAACGGGAAGGUCUGCAGGCAGCGGCCGCAGGUCUGGCGGCUUCUCUGUUGACAACUCAGCUGGUUCCACACCCUGGCAAUUGUGAAGAGUUGGCCAAAUGUUUGUCCACUGAGCUGAUCUCCUCUCUGGAGCACCGGGGCCACCAGGAGGGAGCCAAGACAAUGCAAACUCCAGUGAACAUUCCCGUGCCUGUGCUCCGGCUGCCCCGGGGCCCUGAUGGCUUCAGCCGUGGCUUUGCCCCUGAUGGACGCAGAGCCCCCUUGAGGCCAGAGGUUCCUGAAAUCCAGGAGUGUCCCAUAGCUCAAGAAUCCCUGGAAUCCCAGGAGCAGCGGGCACGAGCCGCCCUUCGGGAGCGUUACCUCCGCAGCCUGCUGGCCAUGGUGGGUCAUCAGGUGAGCUUCACGUUGCACGAGGGUGUGCGUGUGGCCGCCCACUUUGGAGCCACCGACCUGGAUGUGGCCAACUUCUACGUGUCACAGCUGCAGACUCCCAUAGGUGUGCAAGCAGAGGCGCUGCUCCGAUGUAGUGACAUUAUUUCAUAUACCUUCAAGCCAUAAAGAUAUUGUGUUCACUUUUCUGCUUGAGGCUAAGGCACUGUAUCCCAGGCCUCCCAAUGUUCCCGAGCCAGGAACUCUGGGCCCCAUGGAGUUAUGAGCUCCCUUGGAAUUUUGAGCCAAGCUUUAAGCAAGUCUGGACUCCUGAGACCUCCUGGGUCUAGUCAGUAAAAUUCUGCAACUCUAGGAAUUCUAAGAUCCCAUUGGAAGGAAUGCUCUACCUCACAGAACUCUGAACCCUACAGAAAUAUGGGCCUGCUGCCAUUUCCUGAAGACCGGGGCAUCGGGGUGGGGUGAUAAAGGAUACAACCUGCACAGGGGGAAGUUAUUAAAGAGGCUGCAAAGUCCAGCCACCCUGAAGAUACUCCCCAGUGCUCCCCUCCUGCUAAAGAACCAGUUACCCCAGGAAAAUUCGACUCCUGUUUUUCUUUAAUUAACUAUACCGACGGGGAUGGAGUCAUCUUUAGGGGCUGGUAGGGUGGUUAUCCAAGGGCUGAAUCCAGUGGAGCUGGGCCAAGUACGACAGGAGUCCAGAUAAAGGUGUAGGGGCUGCACGGCCGCAAGUCUCCUGGAAAGGCUGGAGUGACCGGCAUGCCGGGAUUGGGAGAUUAGGAUUUGAUUUCAUUUUGGGGCGGGCGGUGGCUCGUGCUGGGUCACGUGGUCGUGCCCAAGCGCUCCUCCUGUUGCCCCACCUGUGGUUGCUGUGGACUGCACACGACAGCAGAUUCGCUGUCCCCUCGUUGGAGGCGAAUGGUCGGACCCCGAGUGGCGGCGCCCCUGAUAAAAGGCCGAGGAUUCGCGAUCAGGGUGCAACUUCACUCCCUCCUCUUUUCUCUCCAGCCUUGCAGCGUGGCCGUUCACAUCACGCGCUUCACUAAGCCUCCUAUCACUAGUAACCUUUCAGCGCAUUGUUUAAAAAGAAAGCAGUUUCUGUCCCUUUCUGUAGUUCCUUUAAGUUCAGGAUGUAAGCGAAGCCUUCCAUUAAGUAAAGGUGAGUGUCGUUUCGUCUCA